UGGCUCAUGUCACCUUGUGAGGGUCAACUGCUAAAUUUCCAGAAAUUUUUUGAGCCAGUUGUUAACCGCAGAUAUUAUUAAAUGUUGUAUUAUAUAUUUAACUUACAAGUAAAUAAAUUACAUUAAAAACAAUAGUAAUAAAUACUCAAAACUCAUUACUUCCUAAUUAUUUACUAAAUCUUACUAUUGUGUGUGUACUUGAAGUUGUUUGCAUCCAUGGCAACUAUAUGAUGGAAAUCCUGCAUAGUGGUAUGCUGCUAUAUAUUUGUGUUUCUCUUUGCAACCCUGUGUUCAGUGAUGUCACAUUAGUAAUUUGAAAUCUGACAUAGUAGGACUUUUUACACAAUAGAAAUCUGCUACAAAUUAGGGCUUGAAUUACUGUCUUAUUUAUUGUCUAGGCCAAAGAAAGUGAUGGAGAAAACAAUAAUGCAGAUUAAACUCAAAAGUGUAUUUUAUCUGUAACAGUUGAAUAAGAAAAAAACUAAGAAAAUGUUUCAGUAUUUGAAAAGUAUUAUAUUAUUCAGCUACAAAGUUGCUUAUAUCAUUGACAAACAAAUGAAGUUUCAAUGCACAUGCACCUUUUUCUUUGUUUCAUUUUUGUCUUACUUGUUCAAGAAGAGGAAAAUGCCAACCAACAUUCUUGUUGGAACUAUACUCAUUCAUCAAUUACAACCAUAGAUUGGCUAAAGAUAUAAGAAUUUGGCCAAAAAUCAAUGAAAGCAAUCUGUAUGAAUCAGUUUGCUAUAUAGAAUUUAUAAUAGAGAAUAUUGUGUAUUUUAUUAUUAUUUGAAAAUUUUAUACCAUACGUUCUUUAUCAAUAACAUUUCUGAUAAACUUACGUAUGUAUAUGUGUACAAUACACUUUUUUCCCCAGAGAGACAGUUAUUAAAUACUUUUUGGCAGACUGCUGGGUACCAUCUUUCUCCUUCAUUUCUUCCACUUUCCUAGGCCAAUUAGGUACUAAGCUCUUUGAUUCUGCUUCUUAAUAUUUCUUAGACUUCUUCACUUUGCAUUCUCAUUGCUGGUACUUGAGAGCCUUAUCUCUCAUUGGUGUCAUAGUAAGUUUCCUAGUAGAUCUCAGCCUCCAAGCUUGUUUUCCUGCCAUUAUUCACACAGCAAUCAGAGUGAUUUUCCUAGCAUGAAAGUGUGAUCAUGUCACAACCCUGCUUAAAAUUGUUCAGUGGCUCCCGUUGCUUUCAAGAUAAAGUUUAAACCCUUUAACAUGGCAUAAAAGAAACCACUGUUUAUCCUCUGCUCCUGCACUUCCAACUUCCAUAUCACAGUCUGACCUGGGUGCCCUCUGUGUAAGUCUCUUUUAUAGAUGUUAUCACACUAUAUUGCUCUUGCUCUUUUUGGCCUAAUAUUUUGUUAUGAAAAUUGUCAAACAUACAGAAAAGUUAACAGAAUUAUACAGCAAACCCAUUACCUGCCACCCAGAUUUCACAAUUGUAUUUACAAUGAACAUAUUUGCUCUAUUGCAUAAUCUACCCAUCUACCCAUUCUUCUACCCGUCUCUUUUCUUCUCUUUUUCUUUCUUUUUUUAGAUGGGAUCUCACUCUGUGGCCAGGCCGGAGUGCAGUGGUGCCAUCUCAGCGCACUGGUUCAAGCAAUUCUCCUGCCUCAGCCUCCUGAGUGGCUGGGAUUACAGGCAUGCACCACCACGCCCAGCUAAUUUUUGUAUUUUUAGUAGAGACGGGGUUUCACUAUGUUGGCCAGGAUGGCCUUGAUCUCCUGACCUUGUGAUCUGCCCGCCUCGGCCUCCCAAAGUGCUGGGAUUACAGGCGUGAGCCACCGCACCCAGCCCCAUCUUCUUUCUUUAUGAUGCAUUUCAAAGUAAGUUGCAGACACUGGUAAAUUUUGUUCCCAAACCCUGCAGCAUGGUAUUGUCAACUAGAGUUAGAUAUGUGAUUACUUAAUUUUUUUUUUUUUUGGGUAAAACUUGCCAUUGCUCUUUACUUGCUUAUUUUCUUCACUGGGUUGAAGUGACUGCAUCUAUCUGUUUUCUAUCCAGUGCCUCACAUAUAGUAGAAACUAAGUUGAUGUUAGUUAAGUGAAUGAGUUAUGGAUUUCAUCAGAUGUUACUUAGAGAGCUUCUUGAUCCUAUAUAAGAGUAGUUUUAUCACUCUUUCGUUCGUCUCCUCAUUCUUCUGCCCAAAAAAGCUGUAGAAAGCAACUUUUAUUCCACCCGUUCAGCAUCACAGACGAUUAAAAUUUUUCAUCUGUUAACAAUAGUUGACAAACUCUCACACUAUGUCUUUCUACAAAGUCCCACAAGGUGGUGCCCAAAUAUCUUUUUUCAAACAACACUUCCUGAAGACCCAUGCAGAGUCCUGACUAAAUUGUGUUAGUAUUUGGCAUUUCUGAAUUUGGUCAAUUAGAAUAACAGAAAAUAUAUAAUUAAGUAAAAGUUACUCAACAUUAAAUAACAUUAUAUAUGUGAUUUCAAAAUCUAUAGUUCUGGAUAUAAACAAUGAAUAAUGAUAAUAGGUACUUUAUUUCUGUGUAGAAUUUAGUAUUAUUAAAAGGUUGUUCAUAUCCCCAAAUAGGAAAAAAAAAAUUCACCUCAAGUCCCCUUUUCUAUAAAUUUUGUCCAUGAAUAAUUUACCCUUAGUAUAGAAUUUCUAAGGGCAGAAGGAGAAACAAACUGUUGUGCAGGAGGAACUAUAUAAUUUAGAUGCAAUGAAAAAAACAGAUGACCCUAUUACCUUAACUGGGAACAAUGUUGUGUAAACCAGCAUUGUAACGGCUUAAUAUAACAUGGGAUAAUAAGUUACUUAAUGCUCUUAAAACACUUUUAUUCCAGAAAUUUAGAAGAGUUAUUUUAAAACUUUUUUUGGAUAUUCUUAUUAAAUCUCAAUACACUGACCAGAAAACCCAAGUAGGUAUUGUGUUUCUACAACUUAAUAUUCAUGCAAAUGAUGAUAUCUACCUAUAUUACUGGCUAUGUUUUGAUUAGGGAUCAGUUAUUGAAGUAGCUGUAACAAUCCCCAGCUACUCAGAUAAACCUGUCCAAACCUGGAGGAGAAAGUUUUUCAACCCAGGGUUCGAAGAGGUGGUGUUCAUUGCCUUUAAUGGCCCAGGCACUAAGAUUUACACAGUGAGAGGUGAGACUCUUUAAUGUGCUGGGACUUAGCCCAUGAUGAUUUGUUCUGAGCCAUUUGCCACUAAAGUUAAAUCCUUAUAAAUAUAAAUUAUUAGCCAUACAGCUUCCUUUUUCUCCUGCUCAAGCACAAGCCUGGAUAGCGCAAAGGCCUAAAAAUUUUCUAGGGCAUUUAGAGAUAAUGAAAGAUGGCCACUUUGAUGCACAAAGACCUAAAUUUUAGUCCCUCACUGAUUAAUGAUUUGACCUUUGGGUGGGUCUUAAUAUCUGUCCUCUAUUUUAUCAACUGUGAAAUGGCAGAAUUAAAUAAAAGUGGUUUCUAAGUUUCCUUCCAGUUCAGAGAUUUAACACUAUUGUUUGUCCCCAAUACAAGAAAAGUUUAAAUACCAAUCAGUGGUUAUCAAAUAAUUCACCAAGAUCUAGAAUAACACUGUCUAAUAUCUGAAAGUAAAAUGAACUAAGUGAAAAAUAGAAAUAUUUUGCCAUUUAAAGCAGAGUUUAGUCAAGGUAUAAAUAGAUCUGAUCUUUCUCUAUUUGUAGGCUCUGCAUGAAAAAGUUAAAACUGCUCUAUCCAUUGACCAAAGAAAAUAAUUAAAGAAAAAUAUUGAACAUUCAAACCUAUGAUAGGACUAGAUCAAUCUACUUUCAGAUAUUUCUUAGAAAAAAAAUUGUAAAACUUUCCAGAUGGCACCUUGAUUUAUUUUUGGUCUAAAAUAAUUGCAUUUAGUCAGGAAUAAACAACAUGGAAAGAAGAAAUAUUAAUAUUGAAAAAAUAUUUUAGAGAAAGAGAUUAAUAGUCAUAAGAUUGGUAUAACGGGAAUUUAGCCUGUCACUGUAGCCUAUGAGGCACUGUGUGUUGCAAAUGUGACACAAUUAUUCAAGCUGGGGAUUGAAUGACAAAUAAUGAAGCAAGAGAUCUUAGGGAGUAAACGAUAUAAAAGAUAAUUGAGUCCGUGUUGCUGUACCCCGAAACUGCUCUAAACCAUAAAGUUUAUUAAAUAAUAGUAACAAUUGAAAAAUAGUAGAGGGAAUGUGGAAGGAUCAACUCAAUCAGAAUUUGGUGAGGGCAUAGGAACUGAAGUCACGCUGUUCCACAUUUAAGCAAUGCCACAUCCUGUAUUUUAUUACCAAUGAUAAUUUUUAUUUUCUUAUUGUCUUUGAAUGCUUUUAAUCUUUCCCUUUGUUGACAAAUAAGACCAAUACAGUUUUGGUGUUUGCCAUGGUUUGCAUAUUUGCCCCCUCCAAACCUCGUGUUGAAAUUUCAUCCCCACUGUUGGAAGUGGGGCCUGAUGGGAAACGUUUGGGUCAUGUGGGUGGAUCCCUUAUGAAUGACUUAAUGCCAUCCUUGCGGUAAUGAGUGUGUUCUCUCUGUAUUAGUUCCUGGGGGAGCUGAUUCUUUAAAAGAGUCUGACACCUCUCUCCCUGCUCUCUUGCUCCCUCUUACCAUAUGAUCUGCACACGCUGGUCCCCUUUCACCUUCUGCCAUGAGUAGAAGCAGUCAAUGGCCCUCACCAGAAGCAGAUGCUGGUGUCAUGCUUCUUGCAUAGACUGCAGAAUUGUAAGCCAAAUAAACCUCUUUUCUUUAUAGAUUACUCAGCCUUAGGUAUUCCUUUAUAGCAACACAAAAUGGACUAAGACAGUGUUCCUCUAAUUACUGAUGAAGGAGUUGAGAGAAUGCCUAGGUCAUAUUCUGGGUCCAAGGAUAAUGAAUCCCAGAAAUUUCAGAGCUUUGGGGCAGGUGUUAGAAAUUCUACUAUAUCAAGCUUUUCUACUGACAAAAAGAAGAAAGAGAAAGAAAGAAAGAAAAAGAAAAAAAGAAAGAAAGAAAGGAAAGGAUCUUCAAGAACAAAUUUCUUCAAAUCAGGUACGAAGGUCAUUAAUUUCUUCCUUGUUAGUUGGUAAUGUUUUUUUUUUUCUACUCUAGAUCAGCAGUGUGGGAGGUGGCUAAAAUAGGGAGAAGCUUGUGAAACUAUACUAUGCCUUAAUCUUGGUCAAAAUAUAUAACUUUGAUUUGUUACCAGCCUUUUUUUGUGUGUAUUUCUAUGACUUCAUGCAGAUACAAUUCUCUGAAAUAUGUAAGUCCUAGCAGACUUGUCUCUUUUUAAAUGAUUCUAGGACCCCAAAAUAUCAUCACCACUGAAAUUAAGAUGUUGGCACUGGUACUAGAAUCAAUAAACACAAUGCAGAUGCUACUAUGGUAGCAUAUUAAAAGAAUUUGAAAAAGUUGAAAAAAGAUUUUCAUCUAGCAGAGCUUUGGAGAAGAGCAAUUUAUUGUAUCACAGACCUCAAGUGACUGAUAAACACUAAAAAUUACUUCUAAUAAUCAUUUAUUUCACAAAUAUGACUGCUUACUCUGGGCUAUUUAUAGUAGUAACAAUGAAAAUAGUGUGCUAUAUUUCUUCCAUAAAGACUUUUACUACAAAAUAACUGUCAGAAGGGCAUGGGCUCCACGUUGCCUUUUUCUAGUCAUUAUGGUUAUCCAUGCUCUCUUAUUUGUUCUGGUGUAAGUCCAAUAGCAUACUAAUUCAAGACCAUCUGUUGGGAUUAAGAUUGUGGUGCAUUGUUUCUCUGGGUGCAAAACUAAUUGUCUUUUAUAGAUUGAUGAAACUGAAGAUUUUAUUUUGCAUAAUCUUCCCAAUUAAUUUAGUGCUGAUUUUCACGCUUGAGAAUGAGAGGUGGCAAAUCUUUGGUUUGAGUUACCCUAUUUAAUGUUGGAGAAUGAAAGGGAAUGGAUGACUAAGUUGGACUCCAACCUCCCACCAACUUUAAUCAAAACAGCUCCAAGGCAGGAGGGCUUUAGUCCAUUUCCCCCAUCUAGGAAUCACCUGUUUGCUUCUUAGUGGCAUUAUUAUUCUGCAUGUUUUUAACCUGCCUCAGCAAAAAGAGAGUUGACCUGAAAAGAUGCUACUUCCUUGUCUCUUGAUUCUCAUCUUACAAAAGUAAAAAGUGUGACUAACACCCAUAGGCUAUCAGGUAAAUACAUGGUUGUUCCCUAGGAAAUUCCGUUGUUAUUUCUGCAUUAUACCCACCGUUUCUUCUUUCUGUUACCAAAGCCUCACAAAACUUCCUCAGUUCCUCGAAACCUGUUUUGUGAGGAGGAGACAGUGAAAACACAGACGUUCGCAUAGAUACUUAAUGAUGCAGUAGUUGUUAUAAGUGAGGCUCACAGGUCUUACCAGCCUGAGUUAAAAGUUCAUUUUGCCAUUCUCUGGUUUUAGUAUGACAGCGGACAAGUUACUGAACCUCUCUCUGCCUCCAUCUUGGAAAAAUUCGAAUUCUUACAACAUCUACUAAGUACAAGGGGUCCUGGAAUAAUAUUUUGUUCAAUGUCAUUUUGUUAUAACAUUGAUGAGAAAAAAAAUUCAAUUCCUGGGCCAGGCUCACUGUGUGGAGUUGACAUGUUUUCCCCAUGUCUGUGUGGGUUUUCUCCAGGUCCUGGAGUUUCCUCCCACAUCCCAAAGCUUUGCCCAUUAGAUGCAUUGGUGUGUCUACAUGGUGCCUGUCUGAGAGAGUGGGUGGGUGUAUGAGUGCCCUUUGACAGUACUGCAUCCUGUCCAGGGCUGGUUCCUGCCUUGUAUCCUCAGCUGCUGGGACAGGAUCUGGUCAACCGUGACCCUGAACUGGAAUAUGCAGGUGCUACAAGACAGAUGAUUUUUCACCAUCUACCAUAAUGUGGAACAGAUAUUUUGUCUUCUAUCUCCUGCUUUUGUCAGCGUUUACGAGUCAAACAGUAUCCGGACAAAGAAAGAAAGGACCAAAAUCAAAUUUGCUUGCAAGGAAAAGUGAUGUCCAGGGCUCCAUUUGUUUCAUAGAUAUUGUCUUCAUCGUGGACAGCUCUGAAAGUUCUAAAAUUGCCCUCUUUGAUAAACAGAAAGAUUUUGUGGAUAGCUUGAGUGACAAGAUUUUCCAAUUGACUCCUGGUCGCUCCUUGGAAUAUGACAUCAAACUGGCAGCCCUUCAGUUUAGCAGCUCUGUCCAAAUUGAUCCACCUUUUUCUUCCUGGAAGGACCUGCAGACAUUUAAGCAGAAGGUCAAGUCUAUGAAUUUAAUAGGGCAAGGUACCUUCUCUUAUUAUGCCAUUUCCAAUGCCACUAGGCUACUUAAGAGAGAAGGGCGUAAGGAUGGUGUGAAAGUGGUUUUGCUGAUGACUGAUGGCAUCGACCAUCCAAAGAAUCCAGAUGUUCAAAGUAUUUCUGAAGAUGCCAGAAUUUCAGGAAUAUCAUUUAUCACCAUUGCACUUUCUACGGUAGUCAAUGAAGCCAAACUUCGUUUGAUUUCUGGGGAUUCAUCCAGUGAACCCACUUUACUGUUGAGUGAUCCAACCCUUGUAGAUAAAAUUCAAGAUCGUCUGGAUAUCUUAUUUGAAAAGAAGUGUGAACGCAAGAUUUGUGAAUGUGAGAAGGGAGAUCCAGGUGAUCCAGGGCCUCCUGGUACACAUGGAAAUCCAGGUAUCAAAGGUGAGCGAGGACCAAAAGGAAACCCGGGCAACGCUCAAAAAGGAGAAGCUGGAGAAAGAGGUCCAGGGGGAAUUCCUGGGUACAAGGGUGACAAGGGUGAACGUGGGGAAUGUGGUAAACCAGGGAUAAAAGGUGACAAGGGAUCCCCAGGGCCAUAUGGACCAAAGGGACCCAGAGGAAUUCAGGGAAUUACUGGACCUCCAGGAGACCCAGGCCCAAAGGGGUUUCAAGGCAAUAAGGGUGAGCCAGGUCCUCCUGGUCCUUAUGGUUCUCCAGGAGCUCCUGGAAUUGGACAGCAAGGUAUUAAGGGAGAAAGAGGCCAAGAAGGAAGACCGGGAGCUCCAGGACCCAUUGGAGUUGGUGAGCCUGGACAGCCAGGUCCCCGUGGUCCUGAGGGAGUACCAGGAGAGAGGGGCUUACCCGGAGAAGGAUUUCCAGGACCAAAGGGUGAAAAAGGUUCUGAAGGACCAACUGGCCCACAGGGAUUACAAGGCCUGUCAAUCAAAGGGGAGAAGGGGGAUAUAGGACCUGUGGGACCCCAAGGACCAAUGGGUAUCCCUGGAAUCGGGAGUCAAGGGGAACAGGGAAUCCAAGGUCCUAUUGGUCCACCUGGUCCACAAGGGCCCGCAGGACAGGGCUUACCUGGUUCCAAGGGAGAAGUAGGCCAAAUGGGACCUACAGGCCCUCGAGGACCAGUGGGAAUUGGAGUACAAGGUCCAAAGGGAGAGCCAGGCUCAAUAGGGCUCCCAGGACAACCAGGAGUACCAGGAGAAGAUGGAGCUGCAGGGAAGAAGGGAGAAGCGGGGCUUCCGGGAGCAAGAGGCCCAGAAGGACCACCUGGAAAAGGACAGCCUGGCCCCAAGGGUGACGAAGGCAAGAAAGGGAGCAAAGGAAAUCAAGGACAGAGGGGACUUCCAGGGCCCGAAGGACCAAAGGGUGAACCGGGCAUUAUGGGCCCUUUUGGAAUGCCUGGAACAUCAAUUCCUGGACCACCUGGGCCAAAGGGAGAUAGAGGAGGACCUGGGAUACCUGGAUUUAAGGGAGAACCUGGACUUUCUAUUCGAGGACCAAAGGGUGUCCAAGGCCCUCGGGGACCAGUGGGUGCUCCAGGACUCAAAGGUGAUGGCUAUCCUGGUGUGCCUGGACCUCGUGGAUUACCAGGACCCCCUGGGCCGAUGGGUUUACGUGGAGUGGGAGACACUGGAGCAAAGGGAGAGCCUGGGGUCAGAGGCCCUCCAGGUCCUUCUGGGCCUCGGGGCGUAGGAACCCAAGGGCCAAAGGGUGAUACUGGGCAGAAAGGCUUGCCUGGCCCUCCUGGCCCCCCUGGCUAUGGAUCACAGGGAAUUAAAGGGGAACAAGGACCACAAGGCUUCCCAGGCCCAAAGGGCACAAUGGGCCAUGGCCUCCCAGGCCAGAAGGGAGAGCACGGAGAACGGGGCGAUGUGGGAAAGAAAGGUGAUAAAGGAGAAAUUGGAGAGCCUGGAUCUCCAGGAAAACAGGGUUUACAAGGACCCAAAGGAGACCUAGGACUUACAAAAGAAGAAAUUAUCAAACUUAUUACAGAAAUAUGUGGUUGUGGGCCCAAAUGCAAAGAGACUCCACUAGAGCUGGUGUUUGUGAUCGACAGCUCAGAAAGCGUGGGGCCAGAGAACUUUCAGAUCAUUAAAAAUUUUGUGAAGACUAUGGCUGACCGGGUUGCUCUGGACCUUGCCACGGCCCGCAUAGGCAUAAUCAACUAUAGCCAUAAGGUGGAGAAGGUGGCUAAUUUGAAGCAGUUCUCCAGCAAGGAUGACUUCAAGUUGGCUGUGGACAACAUGCAGUAUCUGGGGGAAGGCACAUACACAGCCACUGCUCUGCAAGCAGCCAACGACAUGUUUGAAGAUGCAAGGCCAGGUGUAAAAAAAGUGGCCUUGGUCAUCACUGAUGGACAGACAGAUUCUCGUGAUAAAGAGAAACUGACAGAGGUGGUGAAGAAUGCCAGUGACACCAAUGUGGAGAUAUUUGUGAUAGGGGUGGUGAAGAAAAAUGAUCCCAACUUUGAAAUAUUCCACAAAGAAAUGAAUCUAAUUGCUACUGACCCAGAGCAUGUUUACCAGUUUGAUGAUUUCUUUACCCUGCAAGACACCCUGAAGCAAAAAUUGUUUCAAAAAAUUUGUGAGGAUUUUGAUUCCUAUCUCGUUCAAAUUUUUGGUUCAUCGUCACCUCAACCUGGAUUUGGGAUGUCAGGGGAAGAACUCAGUGAAUCUACUCCAGAGCCUCAAAAAGAAAUUUCUGAGUCAUUGAGUGUCACCAGAGACCAGGAUGAAGAUGAUAAGGCUCCAGAGCCAACGUGGGCUGAUGAUCUGCCUGCCACUACCUCAUCUGAGGCCACCACCACCCCCAGGCCACUGCUCAGCACCCCUGUGGAUGGGGCAGAGGAUCCUAGAUGUUUGGAAGCCUUGAAGCCUGGAAACUGUGGUGAAUAUGUGGUUCGAUGGUAUUAUGACAAACAGGUCAACUCUUGUGCCCGAUUUUGGUUCAGUGGCUGUAAUGGCUCAGGAAAUAGAUUCAACAGUGAAAAGGAAUGUCAAGAAACCUGCAUUCAAGGAUGAGCAAGUAAAUUGGCCUGUCUCUAUCAAAAGCAUAGAACUCCCUAAUUUCCACAUAUUCACCCAAUACAAAUACAGCACUAUAUUUGAGUGUAUACUGAGUAUUUACAACUUAUACAUGUAAUUGAAUUCUCACUACAGCCCUAGGAUGUACAUAUUAUUAACCACUUAUAUAGGUAAGAAAGCUGAGGCUCUGAGAAGUUUAGUAACUUGUCAACUGUCACCCAACUAAAAAGUUUCAGAGCUGAGGAUUUAGACUUAGAGCUGUGUAACUUCAAUACACAGACUCUAUCUACUUCACAACCUGCAAUGUGAUUCUGAUUCCUUUAAUUCCUGUUGUAUGUACUAUGUCAGCUCAAACCCCUACCCCUGUCCCUGCCCAUACCUCCACCCACUCACCUCCCUAACCUCCUUAUGUCCCUCGCAGUAGCAAGAUGUAGGUGAUAGGAAGGACUUCGGUGUGAGAAUUAGAAAUGAUGUAAAUGUUUACGCAGGAGUGCUGGGAUAGGAGUCGGGAUGGUGAGGGUAGUUAGAUUUUUGCCUCACUUGCCCUGAAAGUGGUAAUAGGGAGAAACCAAUCUGAAUUACAAUUACUUAAAUGUAUCACAGACUGUCACUUUGUAUUCCUCCAACAUGUUUGGUAACAAGUGUUUAAUGUAUGUUAAAACAAAGAAGGUUUUUAUACCCUUCCAUUAAAAUAUGUCAGUGGGCCCUUCCAUUUUAUGGAGUGGAAUGGGAAGGCCCUUGACAGCCAGGAACCA